GCGCUCGCCUGCGCUGUGGUGGGAGCUGGAGCGGAGGUAGAAGCUGAGGCUCCAGGGGACCCGACGACACUUGCUGGCUGCGUGACCUCGGUCACACCAGGGCCAUUUUGCUGACAAGACAACAGAGGCCGGGCGCGGUGGCUCACGCCUGUAAUCCCAGCACUUUGGGAAGCCGAGGUGGGCGGAUCACAAGCUCAGGAGUUCGAGACCAGCCUGACUAACAUGCGAGAAGUGAGUCCUGAGGUCCGGCCCACACUGAAGGAGAGGAGAUCCUAGCAGGGCUGGGGAUUAUCAGGAGCCCUCCCAAAGGCCACUGAAGAGAGCAGUCAAGAUGGUGGAUGGGGUCAGCUGGCUGCCCAGAGGUCAUCUGAUAAGGACUAGGAGCUGUUAGUGGCCCUGGCGAUAGCAGAUCUGGGCUGGCCGGUGUGUCUGGAGUCAGACACUACAUUGAAGUGUGUUGACAGCAUAGGACAGAUGUGGUUGGAUGUUACUUUGGAGAUUCAGUUACAAAAAGACUGCAGCUUUGCUCACUCUGAGAGAAGGCAGCAUCCAUGUCUUGAGGACACUCAGGCAGCCUGGGACAGGCUUGGGGAGUGAGGAGCUGGGACCCCAGCCAACAGUCAUGCUGGACUUGCUCCAGGACACAUCACCUUGGGGUUUGCUCUUCCCAGGUCAGUAGGCAUCCAGCGCUGGGGCAGCUGCUUCAGGACAUCGCCGAGGACAAGUCUCCUCCCCAUUCUGGUUCCACCAUCUGUAGCCUGUGGCUUUCAUCCUCAAGGGCUCCAUGCGACCGCUGCACAUCCAGGGCUGGCUGCUGGCGGGAUGGACACCCUGGAGGAGGUGACUUGGGCCAAUGGGAGCACAGCGCUACCCCCACCCCUGGCACCAAACAUCAGUGUGCCUCAUCGCUGCCUGCUGCUGCUCUACGAAGACAUUGGCACCUCCAGGGUCCGGUACUGGGACCUCUUGCUGCUCAUCCCCAAUGUGCUCUUCCUCAUCUUCCUGCUCUGGAAGCUUCCAUCUGCUCGGGCGAAGAUCCGCAUCACCUCCAGCCCCAUUUUUAUCACCUUCUACAUCCUGGUGUUUGUGGUGGCGCUGGUGGGCAUUGCCCGGGCCGUGGUAUCCAUGACGGUGAGCACCUCGAACGCUGCAACUGUUGCUGAUAAGAUCCUGUGGGAGAUCACCCGCUUCUUCCUGCUGGCCAUCGAGCUGAGUGUGAUCAUCCUGGGCCUGGCCUUUGGCCACCUGGAGAGUAAGUCCAGCAUCAAGCGGGUGCUGGCCAUCACCACAGUGCUGUCCCUGGCCUACUCUGUCACCCAGGGGACCCUGGAGAUCCUGUACCCUGAUGCCCAUCUCUCAGCUGAGGACUUUAAUAUCUAUGGCCAUGGGGGCCGCCAGUUCUGGCUGGUCAGCUCCUGCUUCUUCUUCCUGGUCUACUCUCUGGUGGUCAUCCUUCCCAAGACCCCGCUGAAGGAGCGCAUCUCCCUGCCUUCUCGGAGGAGCUUCUACGUGUAUGCGGGCAUCCUGGCACUGCUCAACCUACUGCAGGGGCUGGGGAGUGUGCUGCUGUGCUUCGACAUCAUCGAGGGGCUCUGCUGUGUAGAUGCCACAACCUUCCUGUACUUCAGCUUCUUCGCUCCGCUCAUCUACGUGGCUUUCCUCCGGGGCUUCUUCGGCUCGGAGCCCAAGAUCCUCUUCUCCUACAAAUGCCAAGUGGACGAGACAGAGGAGCCAGAUGUACACCUACCCCAGCCCUACGCUGUGGCCCGGCGGGAGGGCCUGGAGGCUGCAGGGGCUGCUGGGGCCUCAGCUGCCAGCUACUCGAGCACGCAGUUCGACUCUGCCGGCGGGGUGGCCUACCUGGAUGACAUCGCUUCCAUGCCCUGCCACACUGGCAGCAUCAACAGCACAGACAGCGAGCGCUGGAAGGCCAUCAAUGCCUGAGGGCAGCUGCCAGGGCCUGUGGAGGACAGGCCAGAGAGGAGGCCAGCAGGCCCAGAGUCCCCAGGGGAGGAGGACCAGGUCAAGGGACGUUCUGUGGGCAGUAGCCCUGUGUGGCCCUGUUCCCACCAUGAGUCUGGAGGCCCCACCUCCCUGGGGCUCCCAAUCCCCUUUGCCAUCUCUGCUCUCACUGGGGACCCUCCUCCCCUUCCCACCUGCUCUCAUACUGCUCAGUGACAUGGCCCAGGCUUUCCUUCCAGGGCCAUGCUUGGCAAGGUUGGCUGAGGGCACCCUCCUUCUCUGCACCCUUGGCACGAGGGCAGGGCUGGCUCUCCCAAUGCCUCCAUCCCAUCCCCAUGGUGCUUUGGCCUCCUCAAAGCAUCCACCAUGGUGGAUGGACUGAAGUGUGUAUAUUUUCUUGAUCUAUUUUUUAAUAAAAAGGAAAAGGAGCAGAAGGUGCUAAUGUGGAGGUUUUGCAGGAAUACUGGGGCUGGUUCCUUUCAGGAGCCUGAGGGCUGGGUGAGGGGCUGGGAGGCUCAGGGGGCCUCUGCUCAACCAAGGAGCAGUCCCCAGUGCCCAAGCCCUGGGCUGGCUGCUGGGGAGGUGAAGAGAAACAGGAUCCCAGCUGCCGCUGCCCCUGCCCCUGGGCCCAUCUGAGUAGGGGGGACAGACAUGGAGAGAGAGGAGAACUAUGUUUUGUGAGCCAGCCCCUCUCCCUUUGUCAGACACACACUGUUGUCUUGGGCAGCCGGUUCUCUCUGCUCAGCUCCAUUAAAACGCAGAAUGGACUUACUAUUGCCAUCUGUAAAAUGCGGAGAAGACCCAUCCUGCAGGGCCUUUUGUAAGGAUUGGAAAACACUAAGCACGAGUGGCUGGCGUACAGUAAUGAACGAUAAGGAUAGCUCUUAUUUUUAGCCUCAAGAAUAGUGCUUGGCACAUAGUAGGCCCCCAGCAGACAGGACUCGGGGACUGAUGUUUGUCAUAAGGAUGGGUGUGGUUGGCUGAAAAUGGGAGUAAAUCAGAGCAAAGCACUGGGAUCAUAAGGCAUGAGUAGGGGAGAGGGGCCCACUUGUCCCUGCCACUGCCCUUGUACCUGAGUUCGGCUUUGAGCUUUUUGGCAGCCAGAGUGAAAGGGAGUUGCUGCCAGUUAUGUAAUCCCCAGAGUUGGAGAGGAGGAGCCCAUCCAGGACACAGCCAACUGCAUGCUUCAGAGCCUGGGGAGGUCUCAGCCCUGGCUGUGGGGACCCUGAGGAUCAGGCUGUUGCCCGCCUCCGCGAUCAGCCUUUUUUUUUUAGGGGGGAAUGGGGUGCCGAGGGCACAAGCUCCAACACAGCUCAUGUCUGUGGGGCCAAUGUGUCAGGCUCCCUGGGAGGGCCUGGAGGGUUGAUAGCGGACAGGGCCAACAGUACGGCCAGUGAGCUGGACUCCUGGGCUGCAGGGGGUACUGCAGGGUGCCCCUGAAUGGCAUACUUUAUCGGGGCCUCUCAGCUCAUGUAAAAGCCUGGUAAUCAGGGAAGGCAAGCUCACGGCAUUCUGAGUGAGCGGGGUAAGGGUUGGGGCCAGCAGGGAUUUGACCAUCAGAUCCACAUGCAGUCCAAGAUGGCACAGUGUCAGCCGAAGUUUGCUGGCUGCAGUGAAUGAGCAGAGAGGCAUCAACAGAAGAAAAGAGACCAUUUUUAUAAUUUUUAAGUUUGUUUUUUAAAAAUAGGUCAUAUAUGUACAUGGCAAGAAAAAAAAAGGUUCAUGCAGUACAGGAGGGUAUUUGGUGAACGAUAAAUCUCCCUGUGUGGCACUGAAUUCCUCUGUCCCCCUCCUGAAGCACCCAGGGUCUCCAUAACCUUCCAGAGCCAUCCUGUGUUCACACCAACGGAUGUGUAUAUCAUCCCUCUUUCUGUAAUGCUAAUGUCCUGUAGCUCACUCCAAUGGAUCUUGGAGAUCAUUCCAUGUCAAGUGGAGGACUGCUUCACCCCUGCAGCUACAUAUAUAUGGAUAUAUGGCAAUUUAUAAACCACUUCCCUUUUGUUUCUGAAAAAUUUUGCAACAACAAACAAGGCAACAUCAACAAUCCUUAUAAAUUUGCUUUUGGUAACUCAUGCAAGUAGAAUUGCUGGAGCACACAGUCUUAAUUAGUUUUAAUUACUCUUAUUAGUCUUCUGCAGAGAUCAAUAGUUGUCCUCCAAUAUAUGUUGUUUUUCUCCAUUGGAAGAGAAUCCCUGAUUUUUCGCUAGAUACACAGCUGUCUAGAAUAAAGACUGCAUUUUCUAGCCUUCCUUGCAGGUGGGUUCUGGCCAA